AGACCACAGGACAGUAGUGCCUGGCCCCAGCCCCAGGCAGCCACAGCAGGCUGCCUUACCCCAGAAGCAGCUGGUGGCGCCUGACCUCACGAUGACCAGGUGUGCUCUGCUGUUGCUGAUGGUCCUGAUGUUGGGCAGAGUCCUGGUUGUCCCAGUGACCCCUAUCCCAACCUUCCAGCUCCGCCCUCAGAAUUCUCCCCAGACCACUCCCCGACCUGCGGCCUCAGAGAGCCCCUCAGCUGCUCCCACAUGGCCGUGGGCUGCCCAGAGCCACUGCAGCCCCACCCGCCACCCUGGCUCGCGCAUUGUCCUAUCGCUGGAUGUCCCCAUCGGCCUCUUGCAGAUCUUACUGGAGCAAGCCCGGGCCAGGGCUGCCAGGGAGCAGGCCACCACCAACGCCCGCAUCCUGGCCCGUGUCGGCCACUGCUGAGCCUGAGAGAGGGGGUCACAGUGAUAGGGCCACCCUGGAUGGGAAGACCUGGAGGGCAGCCACACAGCUGGACGGAUGCUGCCACAUCUGGGCAUACAGUGUCUGGACGCUGCCACAUCUGGGCAUACAGUGUCUGGACACUGCCACAUGGAGCCACUGUCAUGCAGGUCAUAUCAGAUCUGAGUGCCCCACAGAGUCACAGUGUGUCUGGACAGCCUGGACAUUGGACAUUGCUAAGUUGGGUCACUGCCACAUGGAGUCUUGCCAUGCCUGUGUGCCCCACAGACCUAAUAUAUGUCCGGACAGCUUGGAUGCUGCCACGUAAGGUCACUGCUGUGGCGAGUCUUGCUAUGUCUGGGUGCCCCAUAGUCACAGAACACCUGGACACCGCCACAUGCAGUCAUCAUCAUGUUACUUUCAGGAGCCUCAACACGAGAGCUCAACACUGCCUCCGACCAGUCCCUCUGAGGCCCACAGGUCUGUCAUCCCAUAGGCCACCACACAGAGAAAUGCUGGCUGAGGGUCACUUGCUUGCUCUGUGCCCCAUGAGGCAGCACCUGCCCCAGAUGGACGGGGCUGUGAGGGGUGUCUCCAGGCACAAAGGCCCGAACACAGGAAGCCUGUGACCAUGGCAGCCUUGUCUUAUGGGCGCAUAUGUGCGUGUGUGGCUGAGUCUCUGACAGCUGUGAGUGUGUGUGAGCAGGGUAAGGGUACGUGAGGGGUCUGAGAGGAGUGGGUGCUUGUCCCCCAAACCUGCAUGAAGCAAGAACAACUCCUGGCCAGGCCCUGUCCUCCCCACGUACCCCUGCAUCCCCAGCCUCGACCCAGGGACAUGCAGGGCUCACAGGAGACAGGGCUCAGGCUGCCGGAGCUCCAACCAAACUCUGUCCCACUUCACGCACGGACUGUCCUGGGCAAAGGUGUUCACCUUUCCGAGCCUCGGUUUCCUUAUCUGUAAAGCAAAGCGACACCAGCAAGCCUGUGAGCAUUGUGUAUAUAGCAGACAUGGAGGUCCUGCAGCAGGAGGUGCUCAAUAAACACAAAGCGACUGAAGGAUGGGACCAGCAA